GAGUCCGAGCGCGUCACCUCCUCACGCUGCGGCUGUCGCCCGUGUCCCGCCGGCCCGUUCCGUGUCGCCCCGCAGUGCUGCGGCCGCCGCGGCACCAUGGCUGUGUUUGUCGUGCUCCUGGCGUUGGUGGCGGGUGUUUUGGGGAACGAGUUUAGUAUAUUAAAAUCACCAGGGUCUGUUGUUUUCCGAAAUGGAAAUUGGCCUAUACCAGGAGAGCGGAUCCCAGACGUGGCUGCAUUGUCCAUGGGCUUCUCUGUGAAAGAAGACCUUUCUUGGCCAGGACUCGCAGUGGGUAACCUGUUUCAUCGUCCUCGGGCUACCGUCAUGGUGAUGGUGAAGGGAGUGAACAAACUGGCUCUACCCCCAGGCAGUGUCAUUUCGUACCCUUUGGAGAAUGCAGUUCCUUUUAGUCUUGACAGUGUUGCAAAUUCCAUUCACUCCUUAUUUUCUGAGGAAACUCCUGUUGUUUUGCAGUUGGCUCCCAGUGAGGAAAGAGUGUAUAUGGUAGGGAAGGCAAACUCAGUGUUUGAAGACCUUUCAGUCACCUUGCGCCAGCUCCGUAAUCGCCUGUUUCAAGAAAACUCUGUUCUCAGUUCACUCCCCCUCAAUUCUCUGAGUAGGAACAAUGAAGUUGACCUGCUCUUUCUUUCUGAACUGCAAGUGCUACAUGAUAUUUCAAGCUUGCUGUCUCGUCAUAAGCAUCUAGCCAAGGAUCAUUCUCCUGAUUUAUAUUCACUGGAGCUGGCAGGUUUGGAUGAAAUUGGGAAGCGUUAUGGGGAAGACUCUGAACAAUUCAGAGAUGCUUCUAAGAUCCUUGUUGACGCUCUGCAAAAGUUUGCAGAUGACAUGUACAGUCUUUAUGGUGGGAAUGCAGUGGUAGAGUUAGUCACUGUCAAGUCAUUUGACACCUCCCUCAUUAGGAAGACAAGGACUAUCCUUGAGGCAAAACAAGCGAAGAACCCAGCAAGUCCCUAUAACCUUGCAUAUAAGUAUAAUUUUGAAUAUUCCGUGGUUUUCAACAUGGUACUUUGGAUAAUGAUCGCCUUGGCCUUGGCUGUGAUUAUCACCUCUUACAAUAUUUGGAACAUGGAUCCUGGAUAUGAUAGCAUCAUUUAUAGGAUGACAAACCAGAAGAUUCGAAUGGAUUGAAUGUUACCUGUGCCAGAAUUAGAAAAGGGGGUUGGAAAUUGGCUGUUUUGUUAAAAUAUAUCUUUUAGUGUGCUUUAAAGUAGAUAGUAUACUUUACAUUUAUAAAAAAAAAUCAAAUUUUGUUCUUUAUUUUGUGUGUGCCUGUGAUGUUUUUCUAGAGUGAAUUAUAGUAUUGACGUGAAUCCCACUGUGGUAUAGAUUCCAUAAUAUGCUUGAAUAUUAUGAUAUAGCCAUUUAAUAACAUUGAUUUCAUUCUGUUUAAUGAAUUUGGAAAUAUGCACUGAAAGAAAUGUAAAACAUUUAGAAUAGCUCGUGUUAUGGAAAAAAGUGCACUGAAUUUAUUAGACAAACUUACGAAUGCUUAACUUCUUUACACAGCAUAGGUGAAAAUCAUAUUUGGGCUAUUGUAUACUAUGAACAAUUUGUAAAUGUCUUAAUUUGAUGUAAAUAACUCUGAAACAAGAGAAAAGGUUUUUAACUUAGAGUAGCCCUAAAAUAUGGAUGUGCUUAUAUAAUCGCUUAGUUUUGGAACUGUAUCUGAGUAACAGAGGACAGCUGUUUUUUAACCCUCUUCUGCAAGUUUGUUGACCUACAUGGGCUAAUAUGGAUACUAAAAAUACUACAUUGAUCUAAGAAGAAACUAGCCUUGUGGAGUAUAUAGAUGCUUUUCAUUAUACACACAAAAAUCCCUGAGGGACAUUUUGAGGCAUGAAUAUAAAACAUUUUUAUUUCAGUAACUUUUCCCCCUGUGUAAGUUACUAUGGUUUGUGGUACAACUUCAUUCUAUAGAAUAUUAAGUGGAAGUGGGUGAAUUCUACUUUUUAUGUUGGAGUGGACCAAUGUCUAUCAAGAGUGACAAAUAAAGUUAAUGAUGAUUCCAAAUUUGUGUCAUUGCAGUACUAAAUCUAUUUUAUAUUGUAAAAACCUAACAAAACAGGCUUUUCUUUCAUCAGGAUUGGCUGUUUUGUUGUACAGAUAAUUUCAUGGUGUUUCUUUUACACUUGUUUAUUCUCGCUGCCUCCUGAGAUUUAGUACUAAUGUAAGGAAGGCAUUUUAAUUACCAUUCUUGUUACUGAAUUUAUAUAGGAUAUAU